GUGACUGGCGGCUGCACUGGCGGCAGCUGGAGGUGUAAUAGUGCGGGUAGUGGGUUUGGAGAAGUUCCGAGGCGGCGGUGGCGCCGGUCAGGACAAGGAUAGCGGAACCGGGCCCUGGGCUUGUCGCUCACCAUGCCGACAGUAGAGGAGCUUUACCGCAAUUAUGGCAUCCUGGCCGAUGCCACGGAGCAAGUGGGCCAGCAUAAAGAUGCCUAUCAAGUGAUAUUGGAUGGUGUGAAAGGUGGUACUAAGGAAAAGCGAUUAGCAGCUCAAUUUAUUCCGAAAUUCUUUAAGCAUUUUCCAGAAUUGGCUGAUUCUGCUAUCAAUGCACAGUUAGACCUCUGUGAGGAUGAAGAUGUAUCUAUUCGACGUCAAGCAAUUAAAGAACUGCCUCAAUUUGCCACUGGAGAAAAUCUUCCUCGAGUGGCAGAUAUACUAACGCAACUUUUGCAGACAGAUGACUCUGCAGAAUUUAACCUAGUGAACAAUGCCCUAUUAAGUAUAUUUAAAAUGGAUGCAAAAGGGACUUUAGGUGGGUUGUUCAGCCAAAUACUUCAAGGAGAGGACAUUGUUAGAGAACGAGCAAUUAAAUUCCUUUCUACAAAACUUAAGACUUUACCAGAUGAAGUCUUAACAAAGGAAGUGGAAGAGCUUAUACUAACUGAAUCCAAAAAGGUCCUAGAAGAUGUGACUGGUGAAGAAUUUGUUCUAUUUAUGAAGAUACUGUCUGGGUUAAAAAGCUUACAGACAGUGAGUGGAAGACAGCAACUUGUAGAGUUGGUGGCUGAACAGGCCGACCUAGAACAGACCUUCAAUCCCUCGGAUCCUGACUGUGUGGACAGGCUCUUACAGUGCACUCGGCAGGCAGUACCCCUCUUCUCUAAAAAUGUCCAUUCCACAAGGUUUGUGACAUAUUUCUGUGAGCAGGUUCUCCCUAACCUCGGUACCUUGACUACCCCAGUGGAAGGUCUUGAUAUACAGUUGGAGGUAUUGAAAUUGUUGGCGGAGAUGAGUUCAUUUUGUGGUGACAUGGAAAAACUAGAAACAAAUUUAAGGAAACUAUUUGAUAAGUUAUUGGAAUACAUGCCCCUCCCUCCAGAAGAGGCAGAAAAUGGAGAGAAUGCUGGUAAUGAAGAACCCAAGCUACAGUUCAGUUAUGUGGAAUGUUUGUUGUACAGUUUUCACCAGUUGGGCCGAAAACUUCCAGAUUUCUUAACAGCCAAACUGAAUGCAGAAAAGCUCAAAGAUUUCAAAAUCAGGCUGCAGUACUUUGCACGGGGCCUGCAAGUUUAUAUCAGACAACUUCGCUUAGCUCUCCAGGGUAAAACGGGUGAGGCCUUAAAAACAGAAGAGAACAAGAUUAAAGUCGUUGCAUUGAAAAUAACAAACAAUAUCAAUGUUUUAAUCAAGGAUCUCUUCCACAUUCCUCCUUCUUAUAAGAGCACAGUAACACUAUCCUGGAAACCUGUACAAAAGGUUGAGAUUGGGCAAAAGAGAGCCAGUGAAGAUACAACUUCAGGUUCACCACCCAAGAAAUCUUCAGCAGGACCAAAAAGAGAUGCCAGGCAGAUUUAUAACCCUCCCAGUGGGAAAUAUAGCAGCAAUUUGGGCAACUUUAAUUAUGAAAGGGGGGUCAAAAAAGACAUCAAGACAUCACCCUAGUAAGACAUAAUGGCAAAAAAAUUGAUUGCAAAAUUGACUGAAAAGGUAUUUUUCAAGCCUCCAAGAUUGUGGAUCAAAAACAGCAAAACCAAGCUCUCUCUAUUGUUGCUAACAAGAUUGCUAUAAUGAGGAAGUUUAGAAGUUAAUGAAGAGAUUUGAUCUCAUUUACAUAUGAUUAAAAGUCCAGCCUUGUGAUAACUUCGAUCAGUUUUCUUCAUGGGACGACACCUUUGAGGACCAUUUCUCUGUGGCUAUAAAAGUGACUGACCAAUGGAUGAGAGACUCUUGUUCUGUACAUCACAAGUGACUUGAUUUUUCAGCAAAAGAUAUGCUUAGUUUAUAUCAGUAGCUGAAACACACUCAGACGCACAUACACACAUAGCACCUAUUUGGCAGUAUUCUGAGAAGCUUAUGUAGCUGAUAAAGCAGUGAAAAAAACUCAGCCUUUAGAUCUACAUUUGUGUGAGUCCAGUUGCGUGAAAUACUGUGAUCAAAACAAAAAUUGCAUAUUUAUUGCAUUCAAAGGGACAUUUUGUAGUCUAACCUGAUUUUCGAAAUUGAUUAUUGAUAAUUUAAGAUAUUUUUCAUAGUUAUAUGAGUUACCUUUAGUAAUGAUAGACAAUAAAUAAAGAACUAAGAAGUUGUCAUGAAAGUCAUAGCCAGAGCAGGUAGAUAAGAGAAAGAAAUAAAGGGCAUCCAAACUAGAAUGGAGAAGUCAAAUUGUUCUCUAUGCAGAUGACAUGAUGUUAUAUAUAUAAAAACAAAACUAAAGACUCUACCAAAAAACUCAUAGAACUGAUAAAUUUAGAAAAGUUAGAAGAUACAAAAUUAGUAUACAAAAAUCAGUAGCAUUUCUAUGCAUGAACAGUGAACUAGCUGAAAAAGAAAUCAAGGUAACCCCAUUUAUAAUAGCUGUGAAAAAAAUCUAGGAAUAAAUUAACCAAGAAGGUAAAAUAUUUCUAUACAAGGAAAACUACAAAACACUGAUGAAAGAAAUUGAAGGAGAUACAAACAAAUUGAAAGACACUCCGUACUCAUGGAUUAGAGGAAUUAAUAUAUUUUAAAUGACCAUGCUACCCAAAGUGAUCUCCAGAUUCAAUACAACUUCUAUCAAAAUAACUGACAUUCUUCACAGAAAUUGCCACCAAAAAAAAUUCUUAAAAUUUAUAUGGAACCACAAGACCCCAAAUAGCCAAAGCAAUACUGAGCAAAAAGAACAAAGCUGGAGUUAUCACACUACCAGAUCUCAAAAUAUAAAUCAAAAAUGUAGUAACCAAAACAGCCUGAUACUGGCAUAAAAAUAGAUACAGAGCAAUGGAACAGAACAGAGAACCAGAAAUUAAUCCACGUAUCUACAGCCAACUGAUUUUUUACAAAGGUGGCAAGAAUACUCAUUGGAGGGACAAAAAAAAAAGGGACAGUCUCUUCAAUAAAUGGUGCUGAGAAAACUGGGUAUCCAUAUGCAGAAGAAUGAAACUAGAUCCGCACCUCCCACCCUGUACAAAAACCAACUCAAAAUGGAUGAAAGACCUAAAUGUAAGACCUAAAACAAUAAAACUACCAUAAGAGAAAACAAGAAGCACUUCAGGACAUUGGUCUGGGAAAAGAUUUUAUGACUGAGACCUAAAAGCACAGGCAACAAAAACAUGGGAUCAUAUCAAAUUAAAAAGCUUCUGUGCAGCAGAGGAAACCAUCAACAGUGAAAAGACAGCUUACAGAAUGGGAGAAAAUAUUUGUAAACUACUCAUGCAACAGAGGAUUAAUAUUCAGAAUAUAGAAGAUAUUCAAACAUCUUAAUAGCAAAACAAAUCUAGAUUAAAAAUGGGCAAAUCAUCUGAACAGACAUUUCUCAAAAGAAGACGUACAAAUGGCCAAUAAAUGUAUGAAAAAAUUCUAAACACUAAGCAUCAGGGUAAUGCACAUCAAAACCACAAUGAGUAAGUUGGAAGUUCAGGGAAGAGAUUUUAUCUCAUUUACAUAUGAUUAAAAGUCAGACAUUGGCACCCCCAUGUUUAUUGUAGCACUAUUCAUUAGCCAAGACAUGGAAUCAACCCAGAAUCAACAGGUGCAUCAACAGGUGAAUGGCUAAACAAGAUGUGGUAUUAUACACAAUGGGAUACUAUUCAGCCAUAAAAAAAGAAUGUCCUUUCAUUUGCAGCAACAUGGAAGGAACUGGAGGACUUUAUAGUAGGUGAAAUAAGCCAGCAAUGGAAAAUUAAACAAUGCAUGUUCUCACUCAUGUGGAAGUUUUAAAAAGUUAAUCUUAUAGAAGUAAAAAUUAGGACAGCGCAUACUAGAGGCUGAGAAGAUAGGGGGAAGGAAGGGAUAGGGAGAGAUUUGUGGGAGGAUGCAAAAUAACAUAGGAAUAAGCCCUAGUGUUGUGUACCACUAUAGCAUGACUAUAGUUAAUAUAUACUUUAAAAUAGAAGAAUAUUGAAUGUUCCCAACACAAAGAAAUUAUAGGUGUUUGAGAUGAUGGAUAUGCUUGUUACCCUGAGCUGAUAACUGUACAUUCUUUGUAUCAAAGUAUUCUACCCCACGAAUAUGUAGAAUUAUUAUUCGUGAAUUUGAAGAAUUAAGUUUUUUAAAAAGUGUACGGGCUGGGCACAGUGGCUCACACCUGUAGUCCCAGCACUGAGGCAGGACGAUCCCUUGAGGCCUGCAGUUUGAGAUCAGCCUGGCAACAAAAUGAGGACCUGUCUCUACAAAAAAAAAAAAUAGCCAAACAUGGUGGUGUGCAUCUGUAGCCCUAGCUACUGGGGAGUCUGAGGCAGAAAGAUCACUCUAGUCCAGAAGUUCAAUGUUAUGGUGAACUGUGAACGCACCACUGCACUCCAGCCUGAGCAACACAGCAAGACCCUCCAAAAAAAGUGUAGUUAUCGUAACAUCACCUUGAAACAACUUUGUUACUGGGAUACAUUUAAUUAAGCAACUACCAUGAAUGUAGUCGGUACCUUGCCUUACGUGCUUCAGUAUAUAUGUUGUUCUUGUUUUAUGUACAGGCUAAAUUUGUAGAUUGAAUAGCAGAAUAUUAGUUCUGUUCUUAUAGGGCCUACUGCUGUAUUCAGAGUUAUGAGCUACGUUUCUUCUGCGUUUGCUGCACCAUGAAAUCCUAAGCAAGACCUAAACCCUUGUUCGCUUUUUCGUAGAGCAGAGAGGAGCCUUCAGGGGAAGUAGAGGUGGCCGAGGUUGGGGCACACGAGGAAAUCGUAGUCGGGGAAGACUCUACUGAAUAAGACAUCAGCAUUCUUCAGCAUUGUCAUGAGCUUAAUAUACUUAAAUUCUACUACUCAUUGGAUUGCCGGGGAUGUCCCUUUAAACAGACUGCUGCCUUCAGCUAAAAACUUAAUGUUCUUUAUACCUUUGUAUGUAUGACCUACUUUUGUAACAGACCAUGGUUGUGUCCAAGGUAAAACCACAGUGAUAUUUUUGGAUGCUUUGUCUGCAAUCUUGACUUGUUUUUGCAGUAUCAUUAUUCAGACUUCAAAUUGUGAAUCUUUUAAACAUCUUGAUAAUUUGUUGUUGAGAGCUGUUCAUUCUAAAAUGUAAUGAAAUUCAGUCUAGUUCUGCUGAUAAAGAUCAUCAGUUUUGAAAGGUUACUGAUUUUCCUCUUCCCUCUUAGUUUUUUACCCAAUAUAUGGAGAAGAGUAAUGGUCAAUCUUAACAUUUUGUUUUAAUUGUUUAAUAAAGCUGCUGGGCAGUGGUGCAGCAUUCCUACCUAGUGUCAUAAAAGCAAAAUACUUACAUAGCUUUCUUAAAAUAUAGGAAUGACAUUACAUUUUUAGGAGAAAGUAAGUUGCUUUGCACCGCCUACUUAAUUCUUUUCCAUAUAUUGUGAUACAAACUUUUGAAUAUGGAAUCUUACUAUUUGAAUAGAAAUGUGUAUGUAUAAUAUACAUACAUACAUAAGCAUAUAUGUGUGUGUGUGUGUGUAUAUAUAUAUAUAUGCAUGCUGUGAAACUUGACUACACAACAUAAAUCACUUUUUAAAUUCCAGGAACGGGUAGUCUGACACGGUGAUUAUCCUUUUGAGGCUGAAUCCGUUAUUAACUUGUUAUUUAGGUUUUUACUCCCAGUAGCAAGGGAUUCUAAGUUAGUUGCACUUACAUGAUUAUUGUUAUUUAAAACUAAGAAUAAAGGCUGCAUUUUCAAAGAUAAAUUGGAAUUGCUGUUGGUGAAAUAACAACCAAAAUACUGAAUCUGAUGUACAUACAGGUUUCUACAGGAAGAGAUGGUAUAAUUUACAAUUUGGAGAUUUAAUAACCAGGGCUACCCAGAAAAAGUGACUUGAUAACAUGGUACCAAUAAGUAAGGGAUGCUCUCUCGGUUUGCUUUUGCCACUUUCAAGAUUUUAACUUCUCAGGUUAUUAAUCAAAAUUAUUGUAUAAGUUAGCCAAUAGAAUUUUUAGGUUAAAACAACAGAUGGGGGGUUUGUGGAGUGUUUAAUGUCAUGGGCAUUUUUAGUAGGAUAGACCCUUUGUUCUGCAUUUGAAUGUUUCGUAUAUUUUUGUUUCACAGUUAAUCUUCCCUCCCCAAGUUUGCUAUUCAAAUCAACUGCCUGAAUGACAUUUCUAGUAGUCUGAUGUAUUUUUCUGAGGAAUAGUUUGUGAUUCCAAUGCAGGUGUCUUCAUUACCAUUACCUCUACACUGCAGAAGAAGCAAAACUCCUUUAUUAGAAUUACUGCACAUGUGUAUGGGGAAAAUAGUUCUGAAAGGCUAGAAUGAUACAAGUGAGCAAAAGUUGGUCAGCUUGGCUAUGGAGUGGUGGCAAUAAUCUCUAAACAUUCCAAAAGACCAUGAGCUGAACCUAAACUCCCUUGGAAUCUGAACAAAGGAAUAUAAAAUUGCCAUUUGAAAACUGACCAGCUAAUCUGGACCUCAGAGAUAGAUCAGCCAGUGGCCCAAAGCCAUUUCAAGUACAGAAAUUAUAGAGACUACAGCUAAAUAAAUUUGAACAUUAAAUAUAAUUUUACCACUUUUUGUCUUUAUAAGCAUAUUUGUAAACUCAGAACUGAGCAGAAGUGACUUUACUUUCUCAAGUUUGAUACUGAGUUGACUGUUCCCUUAUCCCUCACCCUUCCCCUUCCCUUUCCUAAGGCAAUAGUGCACAACUUAGGUUAUUUUUGCUUCCGAAUUUGAAUGAAAAACUUAAUGCCAUGGAUUUUUUUCUUUUGCAAGACACCUGUUUAUCAUCUUGUUUAAAUGUAAAUGUCCCCUUAUGCUUUUGAAAUAAAUUUCCUUUUGUAAUUUU